AUGGAUGAAGCUGGAAACCAUCAUUCUGAGCAAACUAUCACAAGGACAGAAAACCAAACACCGCAUGCUCUCGCUCAUAGGAGGAUGGGGCCCUGUCUGUCUUGUUCUCAGCUGUAUUCCCAGUACCUAGGACUGUCCCAGACACACAGCAGCCCUCCCCUGGCCCUGGACCCUCCAAGGAGACAGCGGCAGGAGCGCACGGUCUACACUGAAAGCCAGCAGAAAGUGCUAGAAUUUUACUUUCAGAAGGACCAGUACCCGAACUACGACCAGCGACUGAAUCUGGCGGAGAUGCUCAGCCUCAGGGAGCAACAGCUGCAGGUGUGGUUCAAGAAUCGCCGCGCCAAACUAGCUCGGGAGCGGCGGCUCCAGCAGCAGCCCCAGCGCGUCCCUGGGCAGAGAGGCCGAGGAGCCCGCGCUGCGCCCCUAGUCCCUGCAGCCUCUGCCUCCGCACCUCAGCGGGGCCCCUCGGGAAUCCUUCCAGCGGCGGAACCCACGAUCUGCAGCCUCCACCAGGCCUGGGGUGGCCCUGGGUGCAGAGCCCAGAAGGGCAUCCCAGCUGCCCUGAGUCCAGGCCCUGGCCCGAUCCCUGCCCCAAUCCCAGGCCCAGCCCAGAUCCCAGGCCCACUCCCUGGCUCAAUUCCAGGCCCAAUUCCAGGCCCAGCUCAGAUCCCAAGCCCGAUCCCAGCCCCAAUCCCAGGCCCAAUUUCAGGCCCAGUCCAGAUCCCAGGCCCAUUCCGUGGCCCAAUCCCAGGCCCAAUUUCAGGCCCAGCCCCGAUCCCAGGCCCAAUCUCAGGCCCAUUCUCAGGCCCAAACCCAGGCCCGAUCCCAGGCCCAAACCCAGGCCCGAUCCCAGGCCCAAUCUCAGGCCCGAUCCCAGGCCCAAUCUCAGUCCCGAUCCCAGGCCCGAUCCCAGGCCCAAUCUCAGGCCCAAUCUCAGGCCCAAACCCAGGCCCGAUCCCAGGCCCAAUCCCAGGCCCAAUCUCAGGCCCGAACCCAGGCCCGAUCCCAGGCCCAAUCUCAGGCCCGAACCCAGGCCUGAUCCCAGGCCCAAUCCCAGGCCCAAUCUCAGGCCCAGGCCCAAUUAUAGGCCCGAUUCCCAGCCCAGCCCAGAUCCCAGGCCCAGGCAGACUCCAAGGCCCAGGUCCCAUCUUAAGUCCUGGCCGGAUGCGAAGCCCUGGCUCACUUCCAGGCCUAGCCCCGAUUUUAGGCCCAGGCUCAGGCCCAGGCUCAGGCUCAGUCCCAGCUCCAAUCCCAGGCCCAGGAUCACUCCCAGCCCCAGCCCCCUUAUGGCCUCAGAGCCCCGAUGCCUCCGACUUCUUGCCAGACACCCAGUUAUUCCCUCACUUCACAGAGCUGCUCCUACCCCUAGACCCCUUGGAGGGAUCCUCAGUCUCCACCAUGACCUCUCAGUACCAAGAAGGGGAUGACUCUAUGGGCAAAAAACACUCAGGGUCUCAGCCCCAAGAGGAGGGUGGCUCUGUGAAUGAAAAUCACUCAGGCCCCAGGUUAUUACUGGAUUUAUAGGGGGCCUGUGCCUGCAAAGUUCUUCAGAUCCCAGAGGGCCUGGAGUGGCUGAUCUACACUGCUGGUGACUUUCUGCAGUGAAUGCAUCACCCUUUACCCACCCUGCUGCAGGUGGACAUUUGCUGUCUUCACUGUGCAGCUAUCACAGGUGGCUCUGCUGUGAAUGUGCCUGCCUGUCAUUUGAAUUGAGCCUGAGCGUUUCUCUGCUGGGAUUGGAGUCGCUGCUCACUGGGAUAUCUGGCAUUAGUGGAUGCUGCUCGAGAGCUUUCUAAAGGGCUUUUCCCAGGGCUUCUGAUGGUCAGCAUCUUCCCCAACACUUAGGAUUGUGAGACUUUUUAAUGUUUGUCGAUCCAAUGACUUGUGGUUUUGUUGUGGUUGUAAUAUCCAUUUCCCUGAUGAUUGAGAAGUUAAACCCUCACAUGUUAAUUGAACCUUAGAUAUCUUCAUAAUGUGUAUUUGUUUACCCCUUUUCCUUCAUUUAUUUGAAUGUAUUCUUAUAUUCUCUUGGCAAUUAAAGUUCUGCAGACACCUUUCCUAUUUGCA